GGGCUGGCCUGUCCUCACCACCCCAUCCGGCCGCCUGCCCGUCCUCCCCAGGGCGGGGAAGGGGGUGGGCCAGCUCCCCCAAAGCCCCGGGAGAACAGGCUGUUGUGGGGGGUGGCAUGGGUCUGGAGAUGGGGGGCGGUGGUGGCCACAGCAGAGGCUCCAGGAGGUGACCGCCUGGUUUCCAUUAGGAAGUCCUGGUCAGCAGCUUGGGCGAGAUGGCAGAGUCAGGGCUGGCCAUGGUAAGGUGGGGCACGGGAGGGUCUGAGGGUGGGGCCUGCCUGCCCCCCCACCCCUGCUCUGCCAACUGGCCACUGCCUCCCCACCAAGACCCUCCCCGAGGAGGGGAUGCUCCAGUCACCAUGGCGACCCUGCGCCCAGCCUGGAGACACGCUGACCCUCCCUCCCCCGCAGUGGCCGAGCCUGCUGCUGCUCCUGCUGUUGCCGGGGCCCCCGCCCGUCGCCGGCUUGGAAGACGCUGCCUUCCCCCACCUGGGGGAGAGCUUGCAGCCCCUGCCCCGGGCCUGUCCCCUGCGCUGCUCCUGCCCCCGAGUCGACACUGUGGACUGUGAUGGCUUGGACCUUCGAGUGUUCCCGGACAACAUCACCAGAGCCGCUCAGCACCUCUCCCUGCAGAACAACCAGCUCCAGGAACUCCCCUACAAUGAGCUGUCCCGCCUCAGUGGCCUGCGAACCCUCAACCUCCACAACAACCUCAUCUCCUCCGAAGCUCUCAGUGGCCCCUCAGUUUCUGCCCCGGUCCCUCCGUGUCGCGGAUCUGGCUGCCAACCAAGUGAUGGAGAUCUUCCCCCUCACCUUUGGGGAGAAGCCGGCACUCAGGUCCGUGUACCUCCACAACAACCAGCUGAGCAACGCUGGCCUGCCCCCCGACGCCUUCCGCGGCUCCGAGGCCAUCGCCACCCUCAGCCUCUCCAACAACCAGCUCAGCUACCUGCCGCCCAGCCUGCCGCCCUCACUCGAGCGGCUCCACCUGCAGAACAAUCUCAUCUCCAAGGUGCCCCGAGGAGCCCUGAGCCGCCAGACUCAACUCCGUGAGCUCUACCUCCAGCACAACCAGCUGACAGACAGUGGCCUGGAUGCCACCACCUUCAGCAAGCUGCAUAGCCUUGAAUACCUGGAUCUCUCCCACAACCAGCUGACCACAGUGCCCGCCGGCCUGCCCCGGACCCUGGCUAUCCUGCACCUGGGCCGCAACCGCAUCCGGCAGGUGGAGGCGGCUCGGCUGCACGGGGCGCGUGGUCUGCGCUAUUUGUUGCUGCAGCACAACCAGCUGGGGAGCUCAGGGCUGCCCGCCGGGGCUCUGCGGCCGCUGCGGGGCCUGCACACGCUGCACCUCUAUGGCAAUGGGCUGGACCGCGUGCCUCCAGCCCUGCCCCGCCGCCUGCGUGCCCUGGUGCUGCCCCACAACCACGUGGCCGCGCUGGGUGCCCGUGACCUGGUCGCCACACCGGGCCUGACGGAGCUUAACCUGGCCUAUAACCGCCUGGCCAGCGCCCGUGUGCACCACCGGGCCUUCCGCCGGUUGCGUGCCCUGCGCAGCCUCGACCUGGCAGGGAAUCAGCUAACCCGGCUGCCCAUGGGCCUGCCCACUGGCCUGCGCACCCUGCAGCUGCAACGCAACCAGCUGCGGAUGCUCGAGCCCGAGCCUCUGGCCGGCCUGGACCAACUGCGGGAGCUCAGCCUGGCGCACAACCGGCUCCGGGUCGGCGACAUCGGGCCAGGCACCUGGCAUGAGCUCCAAGCCCUCCAGGUCAGGCACAGGCUGGUUAGCCACACUGUCCCCAGGGCCCCUCCAUCCCCCUGCCUGCCCUGCCACGUCCCAAACAUUCUAGUUAGCUGGUAAAGCAAUCAGAACAAGAAAAUGAUAAGAGUGGGUUAGAAGGUGAUGAGGAGGCUGGGUGAGGUGGCUCAUGCCUGUAAUCCCAGCACUUUGGGGAGCCAAGGCAGGAGAAUCGCUUUAGGCUAUGGGUUUGAGACCAGCCUGGCAACACAGCAAGACCCUAUCUCUACCAAAAAAACAUAGCCAAGCGUGGUGGCACAUGCCUGUAGUCCCAGCUAUUCAGGAGGCUGAGGCAGGAGGAUCGCUUGAGCCCAGAAGUUUGAGGCUGCAAUGAGCCGUGAUCGGGCCACUGCCCUCUAGACUGGGCAACAGAGCAAGACCCUGUCUCUUGAAAAAAAAAGUGAUGAAAGAGGUAUGGUGCGAUUCAAUGACUGACUCAUUUAAUCAAGUGGGGACCUGUCUGUCUGUGCCUUCCUGGGAAGGGCCUUAGUUUACCUCUGCAGAAGGGAGGAAUUUGGCAAUCAUGGGGGGUGGGGGGCAGAAGGGCCAGGCUGGUAUGAAGGGGGCAGGGGACUCUCAGAGAGGUUGGGGGCUGGCUGAGCUGAGUGGCCCAGGCCUGGGGCUGCCACGAUGCCAUCUAUAACCCCCUGCCCAGAUGCUGGACCUCAGCCACAAUGAGCUGUCCUUUGUGCCCCCGGACCUGCCUGAGGCCCUAGAGGAGCUGCACCUCGAGGGCAACCGCAUCGGCCACGUGGGCCCCGAGGCCUUCCUCAGCACACCCCGCCUGCGUGCCCUCUUCCUCAGGUGCCCCGAGGGUGACCGGAGGGGUGGAGGUGGGCAGGGGAGGGCCUGGGAGGGUCAUGACCGCCUCUCUGUGCAGGGCCAACAGGCUUCACAUGACGAGCAUCGCGGCUGAGGCCUUCCUGGGGCUCCCAAACCUGCGUGUGGUGGACACGGCAGGGAAUCCGGAGCAGGUCCUGAUCCGGCUGCCUCCCACCACCCCACGUGGGCCACGGGCAGGGGGCCCCUGAUCCUAGAGAGGCCCAGCAGAGCAGCUCAGACUCCUGGGACUCCGCUGGGCCGUGGACUGAGGAGACAACGCCCACCAGGGGCCCUUGGUCUGGCUCUCCUGGGCCUCCAGGGCUGGGCCUGCUCUGCCUGCCACUGGCCGAGACACAGAGGCACACAGCUGGCAUACUCCAGGCUCACAGACCACGCCGGCCUGGCGGGACACACCCUACCCCAAACUCCCAACACAGAUGGAGGCAGCAACAAUAAAGCCAAACCCUUCCAGCACUCAGCACGGACCAGGCACCCUUUGGGGGCUCUGUCCACGGACUCCUCCCCACAACCAGUCCAGCUGGGGAAACUGAGGCUCUGGGAUGCUAAGUGGGUCAGGACUGAAUUUUGAGGUCUUGAGGCACACACUGGGGUCACCAAACAGCACCCUGUGCGACCUAGCCACGUGUGAUUGCAGGGACGCCCAAGGCCACCCACUGAAAAAACACUGGGUGACAGAUAUAGGGACCCUCACAUGUAUCCCCCCCCACAGCAAGCAUGGGAAUGAAAUGCAUCCUUCAA